UAAACUGGGUCGCCAGAAGAAUGAAUACUUUACUGCCUUCCUGCCAUCCCGCAGACCCCCAGCGUCACCCACCAUCCCAAAAGGCAUCUGCUGGAUGAUCAGUUCAAAUGAUACUUCAUGGAAACCAACCAAGUGCUCAGAGACAGAAAGAGAGAGAAGAGAUAACACCUGCAUAUCUACAAAGAUAAAGCAGAAACUGAGAACUAGACUUGAUCCUACAUUUUAUGCUGACACCUUAACUCUUUGUCAAAGGCUAUUCCAAUCUGUAAUGGAAGGAAUUCAGGGAUGCCUUCCCUUUCUGUGUGCAUUGUAUAAAGAUAGAAUUGGAGAUUCGCUGGCAGAAAUACCCUCAGCUGCCUCUCUGGUCUUUUCCAGCAACUCCCAGAAGAGCCCUGAUCUCAGGGCUCUUGUCUGCCCCAAGCCUGGGAAGCUUUGCUCAGGGAAAGAAGAACAGAGGGAACUGGGCUGCAACGGAGAUGGUGUUAAUUGGAGCAAAAGAUUUUGCCUACUGGAAAUAGUAGCUGUAAGCGAGAUGAGAUCCAAAGAACCCAGUGAAACUCUUCGGGCCUGCCUGCAGCCUGGCUCCUCCAGGGAAGACAAGACUGAACCCCCAUUGAGGCAAGGCAAAAAAGGCUCAAAAUGAAUCAAUUAACAGCACAUAUAAGAUAAUAAAUGCCUGUAUUUUUUUUU